AGUCGGUGCCAGGUCCCAAAGACGCAGCUGCGCGGGUGUGCCGGGAGGAGCCCCGGAAUCCACAGGCUGCGAGGUGGGCAGCACAGGGGGCCUCCCUCCGAGUCGGCAGCACCAGAGAGAUCGGGUGGAAGGUUCACAGUAGGCAGCCCCGCUUGCUGGCAGCAGUGGCUGGGGUUUCCUUCCCAUAGAGCGGUGUGUUGGAGGAAUACGCACGCCUCGGGAGAAGCUGGCCUCGUAGAAUCAGGAGGGACGUUCAGGAGGGCUUGGGCCAAGGGGAGGGUUCCCCGCCCUGCGGUGGCCCUGGUCCCCCUUGGGACUACCUAGUCUGGCGCCCUGCCUGUUGGACACACUCAGCACCCCGUCACUGGACUGGAAGAGGCCUCCUUUAUCCUCUUUAGAGAGGAUAGUGUGUGUGGAAAGGAUCCAAGUGGAGGCUUCCGAGGAGUGGCAAAGCAAGGGAGCGCCCUCACUUCAGCAUCUCAGCCCUGCUAAAGAAAAAGCUGCUGGGUAACAUCCUUUGUUUUUGCCCAGGGAAGCUUUAGCUGUGAUUCCCUUCAGCCGGCUCCUGAAUGUCAAAGGUACUCCUAAAAGAUGGCGUUAAAACCGAAAAACCAUCGUUGGUGCUGGAAACUCCACUACUAAAGAAAGAAGUGCCAGCACAGGCCAGCCAGAAGAUGACACUGAGACUACAGGUUUGGAAGGCGGCGUUGCCAUGCCAGGUGCCGAAGAUGAUGUGGUGACUCCAGGAACCAGCGAAGACCGCUAUAAGUCUGGCUUGACAACUCUGGUGGCAACAAGUGUCAACAGUGUAACAGGCAUUCGCAUCGAGGAUCUGCCAACUUCAGAAAGCACAGUCCACGCGCAAGAACAAAGUCCAAGCGCCACAGCCUCAAACGUGGCCACCAGUCACUCCACGGAGAAAGUGGAUGGAGACACACAGACAACAGUUGAGAAAGAUGGUUUGUCAACAGUGACCCUGGUUGGAAUCAUAGUUGGGGUCUUACUAGCCAUCGGCUUCAUUGGUGCAAUCAUCGUUGUGGUUAUGCGAAAAAUGUCGGGAAGGUACUCGCCCUAAAGAGCUGAAGGGUUACGCCCUGCUGCCAACGUGCUUAAAAAAAGACCGUUUCUGACUCUGUGCCCUGUCCCUGAGCUCGUGGGAGAAGAUGACCCGUGGAACACUUGCCUGGCCCACUCAGAAUCCACGGUGACCUCUCCGCUUGCCAAAAUAACCGAAGGAAAGACCGUUCACCAGACUUGGCUCCUCUAAACAUUUGCUGUUCAAACAUGUUUUUGAAUAUACAUUCUAUAAAAGAUUAUUUGAAAGACAAAAUUCAUAGAAAAUGGAGCAAAACUGUAUAAACUGAUUUGUAACUAACACUGGACCAUUGGAUCGAUAUUAUAUGCUGUAACCAUGUGUCUCCGUCUGACCAUUCUUGUUAUUGUUAAAAUGCAGAGGAAUCUGGAAAUAUUUAUAUCCACGGAGUCCUUGGAUCCAGUGCUACGUCAGUAAAUAGCACCAGCAUUUUGCAAUUGCUGAUCUGCUGAAAUGUACACAUUCUGGUCUAGUUUGGUCUAUCUUUUAAAGCCUGAUCUGGUGUGAAUAAUCAACUAGGAAAUCUAAACUUGGAUAACACGUGGUGAACAACUGCCUUUAGCUGGUCCAGAUUAAUCAUUUCAAAGACAUCCAUUUUAGAUCACAAGCAGGAAGUCGAUAGUCUCAAAGGCACUUUGUUUCUCCCAAGUAGGCCACCAGGCAGCCUCUAGAGUUGCUUUACCCAAAUCCUUCUCCAGCCAUGACUUGGUGACUCUAAGCUUGCUCCCACCUGCCCCCUCCACUUCCCUCAGAUGAUGAGGAGCCAGGGCUAAGGGGGCAGCCUUCUCUCUUCCCAGUGAUGCACAUCCUUCACAUUGGCUGCUUUGUUCUGGAAUAUGGAUAUCUCAGCCUGGAUGCCGAGGAAGCUGCUGGAUGCUUAAUGGUGCUAGAGGCUCAAGUGUGUUUGAAACCAAGAGCCAGUUGUCCCCCAUGCAGAAAGAAAUCCUGUGUGAGCCUCUGGUAUGAGAAAUAAAAUCUGCCAGUUUUAUAACAUUCACUUUCUGCCUCUGAGGAAAGAUACAGGGAACAAAAAUCAAUUUGUACAGUCUUAAUAUUAAAAGCAGCUUGACUAAAUACCUGAUUUAAAAAUAGAAGACAUCCCCAGUCCUCAUGACAUACCGCAAAUAUCUGUGGGGUCCUGUUGAAAAGAACAAAAUAAAGGAGCCCAAGGGGUCAUUCUGUCUCAGCACCAUCCAGCCUGGCACUUCUCUUCCCAUAUAUCCAUUGGAUUUUUUUUUUUUUUUCCUAAACAAAGUUUUUACACUGAGCAGAUGCUCUGUCAUGAUGGCGGUUGUGCAAUUCUGGUAUCCUCUAAAUUUGUAAGCAUUCAUAAAACAGGAAAAAGUAAACUAUCAUUCGGAAGCACAGCCCAUUCCUCCCAUUUUUUGCAAUGAUGUCUGGAUGUUAUUUUAAACAGUGUGUCUGUGUGUUCCCAAAUCCAGCUGGCCCCACCAGCUCAGAUUCCAUUUUUUUUGUGUGUGUGUGUGAAACGUAGUCUGCAACUCUGCCUCCCGGCAAUUAUACAUGUGUCAGGAUGUCAAAAAGCAAUUCUCCUGCCUCAGCCUCCUGAGUAGCUGGGACUACAGGUUCCUACCACCACACCCGGCCAAUUUUUGUAUUUUUAGUAGAGAUGGGGUUUCACCGUAUCGGCGAGGAUGAUCUCUAUCUCUUGACCUCGUGAUCUGCCCGCCUCGGCCUCCCAAAGUGCUGGGAUUACAGGCGUGUGCCACUGCGCUCGGCCUCAGAUUCCAUAUUUGAACACCAGCUGAUUGAGAGAAGGGGAAUGAGAAGAGCUGGAUGAGUUUAAAUAACUCAUUGUUCAGAUUCCUGAACAGGAGUUGGGAUAAUGGCCAUCUUUUCUUUCCUAUCCUUUCUUCCCCCCUCACUGUGAAAAAUAACAGUCCACCCCAAGUCAUACACUGGACCCAGUGCCUGCGGGGACAGGACUGUGGGUUUCUUGGUCACACCUGUGUUGGUGCUCAAUGCAGUGUAGACAUGUUUUCAAAUAAAACAAAUGAUUGUGUACAA